ACAUCUGUUGAUCUGACCUGACUGGAAGCGUCCAAAGAGGGACGGCUGUCAGCCCUGCUUGACUGAGAACCCACCAGCUCAUCCCAGACACCUCAUAGCAACCUAUUUAUACAAAGGGGGAAAGAAACACCUGAGCAGAAUGGAAUCAUUAUUUUUUUCCCAAGGAGAAAACCGGGGUAAAGGGAGGGAAGCAAUUCAAUUUGAAGUCCCUGUGAAUGGGCUUUCAGAAGGCAAUUAAAGAAAUCCACUCAGAGAGGACUUGGGGUGAAACUUGGGUCCUGUGGUUUUCUGAUUGUAAGUGGAAGCAGGUCUUGCACACGCUGUUGGCAAAUGUCAGGACCAGGUUAAGUGACUGGCAGAAAAACUUCCAGGUGGAACAAGCAACCCAGGUUCUGCUGCAAGCUUGAAGGAGCCUGGAGCGGGAGAAAGCUAACUUGAACAUGACCUGUUGCAUUUGGCAAGUUCUAGCAACAUGCUCCUAAGGAAGCGAUACAGGCACAGACCAUGCAGACUCCAGUUCCUCCUGCUGCUCCUGAUGCUGGGAUGCGUCCUGAUGAUGGUGGCGAUGUUGCACCCUCCCCACCACACCCUGCACCAGACUGUCACAGCCCAAGCCAGCAAGCACAGCCCUGAAGCCAGGUACCGCCUGGACUUUGGGGAAUCCCAGGAUUGGGUACUGGAAGCUGAGGAUGAGGGUGAAGAGUACAGCCCUCUGGAGGGCCUGCCACCCUUUAUCUCACUGCGGGAGGAUCAGCUGCUGGUGGCCGUGGCCUUACCCCAGGCCAGAAGGAACCAGAGCCAGGGCAGGAGAGGUGGGAGCUACCGCCUCAUCAAGCAGCCAAGGAGGCAGGAUAAGGAAGCCCCAAAGAGGGACUGGGGGGCUGAUGAGGACGGGGAGGUGUCUGAAGAAGAGGAGUUGACCCCGUUCAGCCUGGACCCACGUGGCCUCCAGGAGGCACUCAGUGCCCGCAUCCCCCUCCAGAGGGCUCUGCCCGAGGUGCGGCACCCACUGUGUCUGCAGCAGCACCCUCAGGACAGCCUGCCCACAGCCAGCGUCAUCCUCUGUUUCCAUGAUGAGGCCUGGUCCACUCUCCUGCGGACUGUACACAGCAUCCUCGACACAGUGCCCAGGGCCUUCCUGAAGGAGAUCAUCCUCGUGGACGACCUCAGCCAGCAAGGACAACUCAAGUCUGCUCUCAGCGAAUAUGUGGCCAGGCUGGAGGGGGUGAAGUUACUCAGGAGCAACAAGAGGCUGGGUGCCAUCAGGGCCCGGAUGCUGGGGGCCACCAGAGCCACCGGGGAUGUGCUCGUCUUCAUGGAUGCCCACUGCGAGUGCCACCCAGGCUGGCUGGAGCCCCUCCUCAGCAGAAUAGCUGGUGACAGGAGCCGAGUGGUAUCUCCGGUGAUAGAUGUGAUUGACUGGAAGACUUUCCAGUAUUACCCCUCAAAGGACCUGCAGCGUGGGGUGUUGGACUGGAAGCUGGAUUUCCACUGGGAACCUUUGCCAGAGCAUGUGAGGAAGGCCCUCCAGUCCCCCAUAAGCCCCAUCAGGAGCCCUGUGGUGCCCGGAGAGGUGGUGGCCAUGGACAGACAUUACUUCCAAAACACUGGAGCGUAUGACUCUCUUAUGUCGCUGCGAGGUGGUGAAAACCUCGAACUGUCUUUCAAGGCCUGGCUCUGUGGUGGCUCUGUUGAAAUCCUUCCCUGCUCUCGGGUAGGACACAUCUACCAAAAUCAGGAUUCCCAUUCCCCCCUCGACCAGGAGGCCACCCUGAGGAACAGGGUUCGCAUUGCUGAGACCUGGCUGGGGUCAUUCAAAGAAACCUUCUACAAGCAUAGCCCAGAGGCCUUCUCCUUGAGCAAGGCUGAGAAGCCAGACUGCAUGGAACGCUUGCAGCUGCAAAGGAGACUGGGUUGUCGGACAUUCCACUGGUUUCUGGCUAAUGUCUACCCUGAGCUGUACCCAUCUGAACCCAGGCCCAGUUUCUCUGGAAAGCUCCACAACACUGGACUUGGGCUCUGUGCAGACUGCCAGGCAGAAGGGGACAUCCUGGGCUGUCCCAUGGUGUUGGCUCCUUGCAGUGACAGCCGGCAGCAACAGUACCUGCAGCACACCAGCAGGAAGGAGAUUCACUUUGGCAGCCCACAGCACCUGUGCUUUGCUGUCAGGCAGGAGCAGGUGAUUCUUCAGAACUGCACGGAGGAAGGCCUGGCCAUCCACCAGCAGCACUGGGACUUCCAGGAGGUCUCAUAAGACACAGGCUCUGCACACUCAGAAGAGUGGCAGGCACCCAUGGUAACACAGCUGCAUGGCUCAAAGUAACAAUCAAGACAGAAGAACAGGCACCGAUCGAUAGGACUCUUCUAUCUCCUAAAGCUCUUUUGAAGUCUGGCAGAGACGUUUGAGUGGCUUCUGUCCACCUCCUCAGUGACUCACAGUGCGAUGCUCAUGGUUGAACCUGAGUGAUGCCAGCAGCAAGGAAACUGACAGAGCUCGCCGAUCCAUUUCCUGUCAUUCACUUGAGGGUGACAAAGCAUGAUGGUGACAGCUCAGAUAACAUUCCUGGCACAAAAUCCUUAAACUAAAUGGAGCCUGGCUGCCAGGAAGGAGAGGAACAGGCAUUCCAGGGGCAGACUCUGCUGCUGGCUGCAGCCACACAGGAGAGCUUUAAACAGGAUUCUGAACUUAGAGAGCAACAGGAUUUGUGCACCACUGCUACACUGAUCAAUGCCAAUAGUUGGCCCAGGCUGGAGGAUGGGCCAGGCAUCCUAACGCCAUUGGGCAAAUCCAAGGUUUAAGGAAGUCAGCACAGUUGGGGUACACACUAGAGAAAGCUACAUGUUUUGAAGAAUGUGCAGACUCCUUGAGCCCCCACAAAGCAGCCUCACCAUCGGCAUGUAGACAGUGCAAAGUUGAAUGAGAAUCUCAUUAGAACUUCUGGAAGCUCAUCUCUUUCUUACCAGACCCAUGCUUAAGACUGGAGUCCUGGCAGAGGCUAAUAUUCCAGAUAUGAGCCAGAGACAACCUCGUCUGUGCCAGGGGCAUGUCACCCAAACUGAGGUCAUAUAAUUUAAAAUAUAACUCCAAAGUUCAGUAAGGUAUGGCGGAGAAACCUCUGGUGCCUGUAUCACAUGUCCUCAGGCCUUCUCUGCUUUCCGCCACUGCUGCUGAACAGUUCUGUGCAGCCUCAGAUCCCCUGAGCCCUGUGCUAAGUGUCUUCUGCAUUAUGCACCAGGGUUUUCUCUGAAGGCAGAGUUACUCAAACAUCCAGGGAGCAAGCACCCUGGCUUGCUAGGACAGUUAACACUCCCAGGACAACUCUCAGUCACUGAGGGGAUGGGAACCAGUGGAUGGAUGUCUGGCCUCUGUCUUUCAGGUGGAUAAUUAUACAACGCAUCCUGUAUAUUUUUUAAGAGGGUCAACAGAAUCAAGUGGCAACUUUAACGUGUCCUUAUAUUGGCGCCUCCUUCUGCCCCAUCUCACAUCCUCACUCCCACACUCCUGCUUCCCAGGUUCACACCCCUCAUGAACCACCUGCAUCCAGUCCUUGUCUCAUGCUCUGCUUUCAGGGAAACCCAAACUAAACCACACAUGAGCACAGUCUUCCUUUAUAACACAGGCUUUCUAGACUAACAUGGCUGAUGCACAUUCAGUCUCCAACUUAGGCCCUAGAACGGAAACAGGGCCCAGCCAUCCAGACACCUGUGGGAAUCCUGCCACAGGGCCCUUGGCCCCACUCUAGGGCUGGUCCUACAUCCUAAACAUAAUCAAGAAAUUCUUUCCAGUUUUCUUGGCUGGGUCCUUUCUAGCAGGAACAUUUUGAUGGCAUGUGACAGAAACUGAAAUUGAACCGGUUUGGUCCUGUAGAAGCAGGGGAGAUUACUGGAAAAAUACUGAAGCAUCACAUGAAAUUGAAGGAAGGGUUCCCCAAUCCAUGGGAAGGGCAGGGGUGCAGCUGGGCCUCAGGGGAAAAGCCAUAUUCCCGGCUUCUUCCACAUGGAGGACUGUAGCCGCAAACAGCUCAGGAGGCCCAUAUGAAAGAAGACACAUGCAUAUGCAAAUAUCAUAAUGAGAAAGUGUUUCUGCAAGCUCCAGGGAGGAAGAAGCUUUGUCACUAUUUUUUCAGUGAUUAACUGGAGUGUCUAAAACAGUAUCUGCAAUAUGGUAUAUGGGUAAUAGACAUUUGUUGAAUGAAUGAACAGUAGAAGGAGGAAGAGGGAAAAAGAGGAGGUGGGAUGGGAAGAAGGUUUGGGGUAUGACUGUGAAUGAAGCUAUCUGGCCUUCAGCUUUGGAUGGACCUUGCUUUUUCAAGAGAUUAUGGCUGGGGGCAUUAUCCCAUCUUCCUCAGCUCAGAAGCUUGCUGUGGCUCACAGUUUCCUGUGGAAACAACCUGACCUCCUUAGUGUUACAUGCAAAUCCCUCGCAAGUUGGCCCCUACAACCUCCUCUUCACACACCCUCCACUCAGAGCACACUGGCCCACAGCCCAGGGCCAUCCUGAGGGAACUGUCCUAAGGGUCACUGUGCCCUCCUCUGGGACAAACAUACAUGUUUUGAAAGUGGUUUUUUUUUUUUUUUUUUUUUUUGAGAUGGAGUCUCGCUCUGUUGCCAGGCUGGAGUGCAGUGGUGCAAUCUCGGCCCACUGCAACAUCCGCCUCCCGGGUUCAAGUGAUUCUCCUGCCUCAGCCUCCUGAGUAGCUGGGACUACAGGUGCAUGCCACCACACCCAGCUAAUUUUUGUAUUUUUAGUAGAGACGGUUUCACCAUGUUGGCCAGGAUGGUCUCGAUCUCUUGACCUCGUGAUCUGCCCUCCUCGACCUCCCAAAGUGCUGGGAUUACAGGCGUGAGCCACCGCGCCCAGCCUGAAAAGGAUUUUAAAUUGUUUUUAUGAGGGAAACAUGUUAUCUUGUUCAUGUAAUACUCUAUAGCAGAACCCAGUAGGGAAUAAUAGAUUCUGCAUAUAUAGGAAUACUCUUCUAACUCUGGAAAGAAAAGCAUAAUAUUAUAUAGAUUAAAAAGAAAAGUAUUUAUAGCAAUAAAUAAUUGAAAUGAAAGUAUUACAGGAAUAAAAUAUUUUAAAUAAAAAUUAGGUGGGAAAAUUGACAUUGUACUUGAUGAGUUGUGAGGCCUAUGGCUUGUAAUUUUUCUGAGAAAGUUAGAGAAGCAUGAAAUGAGUAUAUUCACAGUGUUUGCUGUUGUUGUUGUUGCUAUAUAUUUACCAUUGUGUUUCCUCUUCAGAAUGUGGCUUUUCAUACAUAAAUACAUUUGCACAGAGUAAAUUUUGGAUGAAUUUGAACCAGGGGGUAGAAGAUAUAUCUUAUAUUCCAGCAAAGACUGUAGUGUGUGUGUGUGUGUGUGUGUGUGUGUGUGUGUGUGUCUGUUUGUAAGACCUUCUGCUAAAGGAUGCUUGCAGACAAAGUCCUUAUCAGCCAUGACACAGAAAUAUGGAUCAAUAAGUGUGUAUUGAAUGGAUGAACAAGAAAAGAGAAAAGCAGCAAUUUAGACUGUGUGCCUAACACUGUGCAAGGUGCUUAGCACAUGUCUUUUCAUUUAAUCCUCACAACCACCCUGCAAGGUGAUUUUCAUCAUGUCUAAUUUACAGAAGGAGAAACUGUGGCUUGCCCAAGGUCACAAAACUAACAAAGGAUUCAAAUCCAGGAACGUCAGAUCAUGAUGCCUUUGCCGUCUGCAUUGAGCGCCGCAGCCCUAAUUGGUUAGCUUGCGCCACCUAGUGGCAGAACUAAAACAGGAACCAGGUCAGCCUGCAACAAAUAUUAAAGCAGCAGGCUGCACCCUUCAACGGGGCUUGUGAAACCUGGAGAAGCACAGGCACGCCUGUGACCCACACUCACUCCAACCCCACAACUGAUAAAAGACAACGCAAGGCCCAGAAUCAGAUAACCUGGGAAAGUGUGUUGUAAAUGAAGCAUCAUUUCCUCUUGAAAUACAUUUUUUGUCUUCCUGUACUGGGAACAUAAAAGUCCCUCACCAUCCCCUUGACCUCUCAGCAUUUCCAGGGCUUCCCUCGACCUCAGUCUGCUGUCCCCCUCCCGGACCCAGCACCUUUUUAGCACUGAGGAUCUAACCUUGUGCUCAUGAGGCCUGGCUUGGUGGCGACACGUCACCCAGCACACACAGGGGCUGUCCCAGGAACGAAGUGGCAUGCACAUGUGGCACUCCAGGCUUCCAGCUCAUCUGUGAACAGCUGCGGUCAUUUGGUGGCGAAAACUCUACAGCCCACCUACCAGCCUCCUAGCCGCAGUCCCACCUGCUCCAUUUUCACUACAGUCGUUUUUGAAGAGGGGCGGUGUUUCUCCUGCAGUUUACUGACAAUGUUUACAGAGAAGCUAUCGUUCAAGCUACUGUUCACUGCCUCCCUCCCCCGCUCAAAACACAUGAAAAGUUAUUCUGCCCUAGAAAAUAUAGGUGCCUUAGCCAGCAGGCAAAUAAACAUCCUCGUGGUCUA